GUCUCUCUGGCCGCCUCUGCCUCCAUCUCUGUGUGUCUGCGUCUUCGUCCCUGUCUCUGAGUUUCGGCUUGGGUGUCUCUCUCCUACCCCGGUCUCUCUGUGUCCUGUCUGUCUCUGCCUCUCCUGUCCCUCUCUCCGCAGCGCCCUCCCCGUCUCUGUCUCUCUGAGUCCCUAGCUCGCUCCUUCUCUAAAUCUGUGUCCCUAUAGCCCCCUGCGUCUCUCUGACUCUCCCUGCAUCUCCCUCCCCUGUCUGUGAAUUUCUCUGUGUCCAUCUUCUGUCCUCUCCCUCCGGUCCCUGGCUCCCUGCCGUGCUUCCUCUGGUCCCGAGUCUCCCCUUCAUCUCCCGCCUGGCCCUCCUCCCUGUGGCCACCUCCUCCCUGCGGCCUCUCGGGGCAGGGUGGGCGCCUGGGCGUGCUGCGCGCGCCCUCAUGUGGCCGGCAGACGCUGCGUGUGAGCGCCAAAAGGGGAGUGCUGGGGAGCGGGGGACGCUGGUGUUCGCGGUGACACUGGGAAAUGGCGUGUGACACCUGGAGGCUGUGUGAGUGUGUACUGCCGGGAGACGGCGUGAGACAUCUGGAGAGUGUGUGAGUGUGUACUGCCGUGAUGGUGUGUGACUCCAGGAGAUCUGUGAGUGUGUACUGCUGUGAGAUGGUGUACGACGCCAGGAAACUGUGUGAGUGUCGACUGCCGUGAGAUGGUGUGCAGUGCCAGGACCAGGACACCAUGAGUGUGUACUGCCAUGAUGGUGUACUGGUGAGAUGGUGUGUGGUGCUGGGAGUCUGUGUGUGACUGAUUGAUAUGAGAUUAUGUGCGACAAGGAGAGACUGAGUGGGACUGCAUAUGUCAGAGAUGACAUGUCGCUGACUGUGUGUGACACUGAGAUUACUGGUGAUGCUGAGAGAUUGUGGGUGACUGUGUGUGCUGAUGAAAGGUUAUGUGUGAUCGGGUGUGGGAGAGACACUCUUUGGGGCUCUGUAUGGGACAUUGAGAGACCGUAUGUGGGAGUGAGAGACCGUGUGUGACGGUGCGUGUGAGGGGGCAGUGUGUGUGGCUGUGUGCAACAUGGUGAGCAUACGGUGCUGUGUGUGUCACACAAGUAGAUUCUGUGUGAGAGAGAGUGAGACUGAUGACUGAUGUACACUGAGAGGUGGUGUGGGCAGGUGUCAUGAGAGGCACAUAGGGGGCCUGGGUGGGACAGACACAGUGAGUGUCAGUCUGUGUUGGCCACUCUGUGUAUGGCUUGUGAAAAAGUGCGUGAUCCGGGCACAUUGCUGUAAUCCCAGCACUUUGGGUGGCUGAGGCGGGAGGAUCCCUUGAGGCCAGGAGUUUGAGAUCAGCCUGGGCAACAUAGGGAGACCCCUCCCCCCACCCCCGCCGUCUCUACCAAAAUAAAAAUAAAAGAAAUUAACCAGGUGCGGUUAUGUACCUCUGUGGUCCCAGCUACUGGGAGGCUGAGGUUGGAGGAUCGCUUGAGCCUGGGAAGUGGAGGCUGCAGUGAGCUAAGAUCGCGCCACUGCACUCCAGCCUGGGUGACAGAGAGAGAGACCUUGUCUCAAAAAACAAAACAAAACUGCGUGACUAUGUGUGACACUGAGCUGGUGAGAGAUGGCAGCGUUGUGACAGUGCAUGCGAGAGUUUGCGGCUGUGCAGGGCACUCGGAAGCGAGAGCGUGAGGGAGGCCUUGUGUGUAGAAGGCAAGAGAUGAUGGAGAGGUGGGAGUGAGUGUGUGAAACGCUGCGAGCUUGUGUGGGACUCUGUGAGACACUGAGCCAUCGUGGGUAGCUAGGUAUGACACCAGGAGAUGGGUUGCGUGCGUGUGUGUGACAGGGACAGACUGUGUAUGGAGGGAAUGUGUCAGAUGCGUGUGACACCAGGAGACUGUGAGAGAAUGUAUGUGACCUUCCAUGGUUGUCACUGGACAGGCGACUGGGUGUUACUAUGAAAUACUAUAAAACAGUGUGUACUUGACAGGUUGUAUUGGGUAAUUGCAUGCCACCGUGAGACACAGAAAGUGUGAGACUGGGACAGGGUGUGAGAUUGAGAGAGUUUAAAUGGCAUGCAAGGCCAGGCGCGGUGGCUCACGCCUGUAAUCCCAGCACUUUGGGAGGCCGAGGCGGGUGGAUGACCUGAGGUCAGGAGUUCAAGACCAGCCUGGCCAACAUUGUGAGACCCUGUCUCUACGAAAAAUACAAAAAUCAGACGGGCGUGGUGUCAGGCACCUGUAAUCCCAGCUACUCAGGAGGCUGAGGCAGGAGAAUGGCUUGAACCCAGGAGGCGGAGGUUGCAGUGAGCUGAGAUUGGGCCACUGCACUCCAGCCUGGGCAACACAGCGAGACUUCAUCUCAAAAAAAAAAAAAAAAAAAGGCAUGCAAAUGUGUGUGACAUUUGGAGACAUUAUGUGUGACACUGUGGUACAUUUGGUGCUCUGAGAUAAUUUAUCUGACUGUGUAGCGCUUGGAGCUGCCAUUGGUGGCGGCUGUGUGUGGCAUUUGGGGCAACCGUGUGAGGUUGUGUUGAGCAAGGUCAUUCGUGAGGUUGUGUGGUGCUACCGUGUGACAGGGCAAGAUAGUUUUUGUCUGUGUGAGGGACAGUGAGCAUGAGGCUGGAGGGGGGUGGUGACACCGAGGUGGCGAGUGUGGCUGAGUGAGCGGCUCUGUGGGACACACUGGAGAGCCCCCACUCCCGCGCGUCUUUUAACCCCUUCCCCGCCGCAACCAUGUCCAACAACAUGGCCAAGAUUGCCGAGGCCCGCAAGACGGUGGAACAGCUGAAGCUGGAGGUGAACAUCGACCGCAUGAAGGUGUCGCAGGCAGCAGCGGAACUCCUGGCUUUCUGCGAGACGCAUGCCAAAGAUGACCCGCUGGUGACGCCAGUACCCGCCGCGGAGAACCCCUUCCGCGACAAGCGCCUCUUUUGUGUUCUGCUCUGAGCCCUCCGGACAGCUUACCCUCCCCUGCCAAAGUAUGGAUCCAAUAAACUUGGUAACUGUGGUGGUGCCUGUGCUUUCAGGGAGACUGAGGCACGCACAGAGCUUGGGGCCACCGUAGGGGAA